AGUAGCCGCCUCUGCCGCCGCGGAGCUUCCCGAACCUCUUCAGCCGCCCGGAGCCGCUCCCGGAGCCCGGCCGUAGAGGCUGCAAUCGCAGCCGGGAGCCCGCAGCCCGCGCCCCGAGCCCGCCGCCGCCCUUCGAGGGCGCCCCAGGCCGCGCCAUGGUGAAGGUGACGUUCAACUCCGCUCUGGCCCAGAAGGAGGCCAAGAAGGACGAGCCCAAGAGCGGCGAGGAGGCGCUCAUCAUCCCCCCCGACGCCGUCGCGGUGGACUGCAAGGACCCAGAUGAUGUGGUACCAGUUGGCCAAAGAAGAGCCUGGUGUUGGUGCAUGUGCUUUGGACUAGCAUUUAUGCUUGCAGGUGUUAUUCUAGGAGGAGCAUACUUGUACAAAUAUUUUGCACUUCAACCAGAUGACGUGUACUACUGUGGAAUAAAGUACAUCAAAGAUGAUGUCAUCUUAAAUGAGCCCUCUGCAGAUGCCCCAGCUGCUCUCUACCAGACAAUUGAAGAAAAUAUUAAAAUCUUUGAAGAAGAAGAAGUUGAAUUUAUCAGUGUGCCUGUCCCAGAGUUUGCAGAUAGUGAUCCUGCCAACAUUGUUCAUGACUUUAACAAGAAACUUACAGCCUAUUUAGAUCUUAACCUGGAUAAGUGCUAUGUGAUCCCUCUGAACACUUCCAUUGUUAUGCCACCCAGAAACCUACUGGAGUUACUUAUUAACAUCAAGGCUGGAACCUAUUUGCCUCAGUCCUAUCUGAUUCAUGAGCACAUGGUUAUUACUGAUCGCAUUGAAAACAUUGAUCACCUGGGUUUCUUUAUUUAUCGACUGUGUCAUGACAAGGAAACUUACAAACUGCAACGCAGAGAAACUAUUAAAGGUAUUCAGAAACGUGAAGCCAGCAAUUGUUUCGCAAUUCGGCAUUUUGAAAACAAAUUUGCCGUGGAAACUUUAAUUUGUUCUUGAACAGUCAAGAAAAACAUUAUUGAGGAAAAUUAAUAUCACAGCAUAACCCCACCCUUUACAUUUUGUGCAGUGAUUAUUUUUUAAAGUCUUCUUUCAUGUAAGUAGCAAACAGGGCUUUACUAUCUUUUCAUCUCAUUAAUUCAAUUAAAACCAUUACCUUAAAAUUUUUUUCUUUCGAAGUGUGGUGUCUUUUAUAUUUGAAUUAGUAACUGUAUGAAGUCAUAGAUAAUAGUACAUGUCACCUUAGGUAGUAGGAAGAAUUACAAUUUCUUUAAAUCAUUUAUCUGGAUUUUUAUGUUUUAUUAGCAUUUUCAAGAAGACGGAUUAUCUAGAGAAUAAUCAUAUAUAUGCAUACGUAAAAAUGGACCACAGUGACUUAUUUGUAGUUGUUAGUUGCCCUGCUACCUAGUUUGUUAGUGCAUUUGAGCACACAUUUUAAUUUUCCUCUAAUUAAAAUGUGCAGUAUUUUCAGUGUCAAAUAUAUUUAACUAUUUAGAGAAUGAUUUCCACCUUUAUGUUUUAAUAUCCUAGGCAUCUGCUGUAAUAAUAUUUUAGAAAAUGUUUGGAAUUUAAGAAAUAACUUGUGUUACUAAUUUGUAUAACCCAUAUCUGUGCAAUGGAAUAUAAAUAUCACAAAGUUGUUUAACUAGACUGCGUGUUGUUUUUCCCGUAUAAUAAAACCAAAGAAUAGUUUGGUUCUUCAAAUCUUAAGAGAAUCCACAUAAAAGAAGAAACUAUUUUUUAAAAAUUCACUUCUAUAUAUACAAUGAGUAAAAUCACAGAUUUUUUCUUUAAAUAAAAAUAAGUCAUUUUAAUAACUAAACCAGAUUCUUUGUGGAUACUAUUAAAGUAACAUUUAAGCCUCAACCUUGAAUGAUGUUGUUUAAUAUAAAAUGCUUUUAUUUUUGAUGGAAAGGCAAUCAAAGCCUAAAGUUUCCAAGGAACGUAAAAUAACUGUGCUUCUCUGAGAAUGCCCGCCUCACAAGUGGAACAUUUUGAGUUAAUAAUGAUGAUUUUUAUGUUUCUAAGGUUGCUUCCUCUCUGAAAUAAUUCAGAAUCCACCCCCAUUUAAUAAAAUACCUAUGAUUCAUUUCACCUCAAGUUCCUAAGACAAAAAAUUUCAAUUCUGACUUUAGGAGGUCAGAGUUUUUAAAGCUUCCAACUCUUAAAGGAUUUAGUCUAGAAACCAAUUCUAAUUCAAAAGGAUAUUAUUUACUCAUGGCUUUUCAUUUCAUUUCAGUAAUAUUGUCAGAACUUUAAGUCAGUGAGUUGGGUAUUCAGGAAUUAACAAUUUUAGAAGACAAUAUGUUUCAAUAAAAUGAGAAUUGGUUUUUCCUACUUUCCAGGCUCUAAAAUUACAUGAAUUUUCAGGGAGCUGUGAACAUUUAGGAGCACAUUAUUCAUUCAGCAUCUUUUAUAUGCCCAACAUAUGAUAUUGUGUUGAAGAUAUAUCUGCAAAGAAGAAAAAAAGCCACUGCCGUCGUGGAGACUCACAAUCUAGGAAAAGAGAGGGACAGCAAACAACUCAUUACAAUACAUUGGGAUCAGUAGUGUGAGGGAGAAAAACAGGUCUAGGUUCUUUGGAAAACAUUUAGGAGAGUCAAUGAGACUUUCAGAAUGUGAAGUGCAUGGGAUUAGGUCAUGGAAGAAGACCAUGUAUGUCAUCUUGAGGACUUCAUUCUGUAGACCAUGGGCCACUAUUGAAGUUUUGCAUUUUGGAAGGAGCUUAUUAGUUUGUUUUCCUGUUGAUUAUAGUAGUAAUGCAGUAUCAGGGUAGCUGAACUGCAAUAAUAAUCCCAACAUCUCACUGGCUUCAUGCAGUAGGAAUAUGCUUUCAUCACAGUCCAGUAUGGCAGGCAACCUCCAGACUCCCAGGGACCCAAACUUACACUUUACUAAAUGUAAUUCUUUCAUUUGAAUUUUUAAAGGUUUUUGUAUAAUCAUCUUAGUAAAACAUUUGAUAAUUCUUCACAACAUUUGCAAUCAUUGAUUUGGCCAGAUUGGUCUAACAUGGUACCCAUGAUUUUACUUCAUUUCCAGUACUAUUCUGAUAAUUUCCUUUAGAGUCAAUUGAGUAGAGAGUACCCCUCUCACCUAAGCUUAGUCAUGUCCCAGGAAUUUUGGAACUCCAACUGAGAUUUCAGGCUCAUUAUUCAUUCUAGGGCUGAAUGAAUAAUGUGCCCUUUGAACCCUUGUGCCAUGCUGGAAACUGUGGUCUUGGUGUGGCAUGGAAAAACCAGAGGGUGAGGGAUGUGGAUGAGAAGAUGACAGAGAAUCAGACAUGCAGAGAGGACUGCCAGGUCUCCCAGUGGGUUCCAGGGAGACUCAGCUAUCCUUCCCUCUUCUUGAGUUCUGUCUUAGUCCAUUCGGGCUACUAUAACAAAAUACCAUAGACUGAGUGGCUUUAAACAACAGAAGCUUGUUUCUCACAGUUCCAGAAGCUGGAAAGUUCAAGAUCAAGUCACCUGCAGAUUCAGUGUCUGAUGAGGUCCUCCUUCCUCACAGAAAGCUCUCUUCUCUCUGUGACCUUAUAUCACAGAUGACUCUGGGUUCCUCUUACAAGGACACUAGUUCCAUUCAUGGGGGUUCCACUCUCAUGACCUAACACCUCUCAAAGGCCCCAUUUCCUAAUACUGUCACCUUGGGGGUAAGGAUUUCAACAUGAAUUCUGGGGGGACACAAACAUUCAAACCAUAGCAAGUUCCAUAAUGCACCCCAUCAUAUGUGUGUGUGUGUGUAUUUAUUUAUUUAUCUAAGAUAGCUCUAGUUUGCUGCUUUGCAACACAUUCUGCCCCUAUUGCAUUGGUUUAAAAAAAAAGUACAGAAGUCAAGAUGAGACUAUAUAAAUCUUGACAAGUUGUUGGCCGUGAUUGCUCUUUUGUGAUGCAGGAGUGAGAAUCUGGAGAAUCUGGCUUAAGAGGUGGCUGAGAAUUAAAAUAAUAGGCAUGAAAAUGCUUCAUACAGCUCUGUACAGUUGUUGACAGUGCCUUUUUUGAAACCUAUCACUGCUAUAUGUUAGCAAGCAAACACUGAUCUUGUUUUGUAAUGUGUAAUUGUUCACUUCUGCUUUCCCUGUAUCCCUUUUUAGAUUCCACACCCAUAUUAGUGAGAAGCAAGAAAAAAAAAUGUACACAGUGUCCUAAAUGUUGUUUAUCUCGAAUAAUAGAAGUAGGAGUGUAAAACUUAAAGGCUGAUUAAUAAUGCAAAUGAAAAGGCAAAUGGAUUAUUGAAUAGAAAAGGUCUAGAUUCUAUGUUUGAAUGUGGUUAUGAAUUAAUAUGGGCAGAAUCUCUAAGAUUCUGCUAAGUGAACAUUUAGUAGUUUACUAGACAUCUUCUCUUCCACCUAGCAAAGAGUUUGUUGCCCAGAGUUAUAUAAAUCCUACUCUAUUGCACACUAAUCUUUGCAUGUUUAACUCUUUGGGACUUAGGUUCCUAGAUAAGGACUUCAUGUGUAUCUAUUUAGAAAAAGAACAUUUCUUCAUUUCCACAAAGCUACACAGCCAUCAGUUCGUUCAAUAUCUUGUCCAAAGUUAUUGCUAGCGUUCUUCUUUCUGAGUCUUUGUGGCUAAUGCUUUUUUGAGGAAGAAGCAUGAUUUAGUCUCAGCUCUCUAUUGAUCAUUUUAGGCUUUUAUCUUACUGAAAAAAUUAAGCACAAUUUAAGAUUUUUUUUGAAAUAUUUACUGAAUUUUGAGGCCAUAAAUUAUUUCCUGAUAGCACACAUGUAUGGGUUGUAGAUUCCACACUUUUAAUCUUCCAGCCACCUAUUGCAGAUUGGUUCUGAGAAGCAGGAUGAGUGGGAGUGGGCUUAGGGGUCAAAAUUGAGACCUAAGUGGUAUAAAACAAGAUAAUCCUAGCUUCCUCCCACUUAAAAUAAUUUGAUGGGACUUCUGUAUCUGAUUUUUAAGCUUGCAUUUGUGUUUAUAUUUUCAUUGUAAAAAUAUCAAAUAAUACAGUUUUUGAAGGUAAAAAGUAAAUGUUCCCGCCCUUCUACCAUCCUCCUUCCUCAGUCCCAUUCCCCAACAGUUUAACGUGCGAUACAAUAAUGUGUGACACAAAAUGACCUAGUUCUUGCCCUAGUGACUAAGCAGAUGCAAACGCCUUCUUCUUUCCAAACAGUGUGGUCUUAUCCCCGUCGCAAAUGGAGGAUAUUUAAGAAACCCAAGCCAGAAACCCCACAGUCUUCACAGUCACUGUGUCCUCCACCUCCUAGCAGCUUCCUGCUGUUCUGCUCUAGUGGUUCUCUCUGCUUCCCCACACCCACCCGUAAGCCACAACAAUCUUUCCAAAACACGAACUUGAUGGUUUCAUUGUCACACCCCAGCUUAAAACACUUUCCUGGCUUCCCCUGGUUCUUAGGAUAAAGACCAAAAUACUUAAUGCUGCACAGUCCAGUCCCAACCCACUCUCCAGCUUCAUCUUAAUCACACCCCUCUUUGCUCCUAGUGUCCUACCACAUUGCCUGACUUACUGUUUCUUGGUAAAUGCUAUUCUUACUUCCUGAAGAUUAUUUCCAUCUCCUCACCCGACACCCUUCAGUUAGCUUCCACUCAACCUUCAGAAUUUAGUUCAGGUGACCCUUCCUCAAGAGAAGAUUUUCCUGAACCAUUAGGAAAGGCUUCUCUUGUUUCUCAGUCUCAUAGCAUCAUCUGUCUCUUUUUUGUGACUUGAAUAUAAUUAAUAUUUUAUAUUUUGUCCUUGUUGCUUGUUUGGUUAAUAGAUUUCCACCACUAGACUGCUCAAUACGUUAGUAGGGCACCUGACACAUAGUUGCAGCUCUUAUUUAUUGAAUGAAUGAAUGAUUCCUUCCCGUACCACCCUAGUCUUGCCCACUGUCAUUUUUAUUCUGGGUAUUAUAUUUCCCAACCAGUUGUCUGACUUUCUCCUCAGAUCUCAUCCCCAUGGGUCUGAGUGAGUUGCCUUGAAUAUAAGAUUCAGUGAUGGUGUCCUGCUGCACUUAAGAGAAAAUCCUUUUUUCAAGCCCUAAAAUCCUGCCCUCACUAGACUUCUCUCACCAUUUCUCUGUUUGCAUCCUAGCCUUUUAGUUUUGGCCUCAUAUAAGCUUGCAGCCCUGCCUGAAACAGUUGUCUCUGUCCCCACUCUACCCCCUGCCCUCCACAAAGAAAAGUUAACUCUUACUCAUCUUUCAGAUCUCAGACUAAAAGUUUCCUCAGAGAUGCCACCAUAGCUCUCUAUUUCUCAUACCUUUCAUGAUACUUCAUCACCUGUCUUCAUGAAGUCCUCCUCUAGACUAUUAGCAAAAUGCUCAUACUGUGUCCUCAGUAUUUGGCACAUAAUAGGUUUUCUUGACACUGAAGGAAGGAAUAAACAUCUGGUAACUAUAGCUAGAAAAAAAGGAAAUACGGUAUCUACUUCACUAAAACCAAAGGGGGUUUUUUUGGGCAGACAAUCUUCAUUAUUCAGAUGGAAAUUAAUGUUUGUUGAAUGAAUGAGCUACAUUUCAUGGAUUAACUCCAUGAAAUGGAGUUCAGCUAGUAAGGGUUAUACUUUGAGGCUAUUUCAUCUUGAUGGGCUUGUUGUUCAAAGUUAGAGCCUCAUUUUAAGUAAAAUGUUCUGUGGGGGCCAUAUUAAGAUUUUCAUAUGACAGAAGUGUAUAUAUAUCCACAAAUGUUUCAAGCCAAGAUUAUGUCUUCUUCCAUAAUGCCACCUUCUUCUAGGAUAGUAUUUUUGGGCCAGAUGGUUUUCCACAUUUAAAACAUACCAACAUUCUUUUAAGGCCCAGUGAUUAUCAAAAGGGAUUGGCACUACAUUUUAAAAUGUAGGGGGGAUUUUUGAUUGUCACAGGACUAGAGGAUGCCAUUUGUAUUUAGUAGAUGAGGCCAGGCAGGAUGCUAAAUGUCUUAAAAGUCCGGGAGUCCUGCACAAAAAAUUACUGCCCUUCUUGAUUUGCCAAUUAUGCCCCUGCUGGGAAGCAUGAAAGGAGAGAGAAGAGCUUUCAGAAUGUCAGGGAUAAAUAUAUCCAUUAAGCCUUCAGACUAAGAUGCAGGAAUAGUUUUCCAUUUGGGUAUGAAUACGGCAAGUUCUUAGAACAUUUCUUAAAACAUAAUUAGCCAAAUACUAGUGUAACAGCUACAACUUAUCUAGUUUUAAUCAACUCCAGGGAACAUUACACUUUAUUUAACCCCUAAUUAUCUGAUAACCCAAGUUCUGUCAGAAACACUGCUGAGGCAUCCAGGAAGAUGAGCCUGUGAAAUUUGAGAAUCCUUCAUGUCUCUGGAAUGAGUCCCUAGAUUCUAGCCCUGCAGCUAGCUGACACUCUAAAAAAUUAUGAGUGCCUUCCUUUAGCUCCCCAUAGAAAUGUCUUUGUAUAACCAUGGCAUGAUAUUAUUCUCUUGACUUUUGUUGAGGAUUGAUAGAAAUAAAAAUGAGCCAGAAAUGUUUCUUCAGCUUUUGUAAAGUGCUGUUAAAAGCAUUAUGUCAUAUCUAGUACUUCUUAUCUAAGUAUUUUAAAAUUUAGUGUUAGGAAAAUUUUUUUCACAUAGGAUACAUGUUAAUAUUAGGUAGUACAUCUAAAGAAUUCAUUUGCUUCCCUUUUGCCUUGGUUGCUGGGAAACUCAGAGCCAAACUCGGUGCUUAGAUUAAUUACUUUCAGCCUAGGUUUUUCUGUAUAUCACCCUUUCGGUAGGGCUUGAAGUAACCCUUCAGUUUGCUCAUAUUUUGUUGUGAGUUUUAUAGAUAGUUUACAUGCAACGAAAUGCAUAUAUCUUAAGUGUUCAACUCAGUGAGUUUUGACACUUUUCUUUGUCCAUGUUAACAAUCAUCAAAACAUUUUCAUUGCCCCAGAAAAUACCAUUGUGCUCCUUUCCGGCAAAUAUUCCUUCCCUCUGCUAAAACUACUUUUUCAUUUCUAUGACCAUAGUUCAGUUUUUGGCUAUUCUUGAACUUUAUUUGAAUGGAAUCGUACAUAUAUAAUCUUUUUGUUUGGCUUUUAAAACUCAGUAUAACGUUUUGACAUUUGUCCAUGUUGUUGCAUGACUCAGCAGUUCUUUCUUUUCAGUUGCUGUGUAGUAGUCCAUUUCUUUUGGUUUUGUGUGUGUGUGUGUGCUUUUUAAAUUUAUUUUUUAUUUUUUUUUUUUUGAGACAGAGUCUGGCUCUGUCAACUCAGGCUGGAGUGCAGUGGCAUCAUCUCGGCUCACUGCAAUUUCUGUCUCCCAGGCUCAAGCCAUCCUCUAACCUCAGCCUCCCGAGUAGCUAAGACUCUACAGGCGUAUGCCACCAUACCUAGUUUGUUUUUGUUAUUUUUUUUAGUACAGAUGGGGUUUUGCCAUGUUGUCCAGGCUGGUCUCGAACUCCUGGGCUCAAAGCAAUCCACCCUCCUCGGCCUCCCAAAGUGCUAGGAUUACAAGUGUGAGGCACUGUGCCCUGCCAGUAUUCCAUUUUUUGUGUAUACCACAAUUUAUCAUUUUUUUCUGUGUAGGUAUUUUCAUUGUUUCCAAGUUGGGAAGUAUGAAUAAAGUUGCUAUGAACAUGCAUGUACAAGUCUUUGUAGAUAGCUCAUGUUUUAAAAAGUGUUUGUUUAAUGAUUUCAUUGCAAAAUCAUCUUUAUUGUAAACAUAUCUUUUUGAGGGUAGAUUGGUAAAAUAUACAUAAUAAAUACAUGACAAUGCAGGAGUCCAAGUAUUAUUAGGUUUACAGUCAUAACAAACACCAAGAACCAUUUAUAAAUUUCAGUUUCUCAUUGUUUUAGAAUGGAAGGUCUAACCAAAUAUGUAAUGUAUCCCUUCAAGUAAACUAGUAUAACUUGGGUACCUUCUCAUAUAAAUUCCCCUUAAGGCAUACGUUGCUGUCUUUUCCAAAUUCCCAUUUUGCUUGUCCAAUAGGCAUUAUCAGAUACAACAUGUUCAAAGGCAAACUUGAUUUUCCUCCCAUGGUUUCCUCAUCUCAGCUCCUUUUUUUUUCCAGUUGCACAGGCUAAAAAUAGGAAGUCAUUCUAGAUUCCUCUCUUUUUCAUAAACCUCACAUCAAAUCCAUCAGCCAAUCUGGUGUGCUCUACCUUCAAGAUACGGAUUAUCCAGAAUUCAGCCGCUUCUCACUGUCUCUACUGCUAACAUAGUAGUCAAAGCUGCUAUCAUCUCUUGCUUGGAUUGGUGCAAUGGCCUCACAACUGAUCUUCCUGCUUCCAUACUUGACCCCUAGAGCCUCUUCUAAACAGAGUAGCUAGAGCGAUCUUUUCUAAAUCUAAGCCACAUCAUGUCACUCCCCUGCUCAAAUCCCAACAUUUUAUUCAGAAUAAAAGUCGAACAAUGCCCUACCUGUAGGUAAUCUAGGCCUCCAAAGCUCUUCUUACAUCACCUCCUGUAACUCUCCCCCUUUCUCACUCCUCUACAGCCACACAGCUGCCUCACUUUCCUUUGAACGUACCAAGGGCAAUCCUGCUUCAGAGCCUUUGCACUUGCUGUUUCUGGGCCAGGAAUUCCACACCCUCCUUCCCUCACAUGUAUCCCAAGGCUCACUGCCUUCCUUCAGUUAAGUCUGCUGGAAUGUCACUUCAUUAGGUAUUGCCUGAUCACCUUUUCUAAAGUGAGUCUCACCUCCACCCUCAAUGCUGGCAAUGUCUGUCUGUAGUGUAUUCUUAACAAUACAGAUUAGCACAAUGCAGGCCAGACCAUGAAGACUGUUUCAAGUUCGAGGAUGGGCAAAAAUAAUGACUAGGACUUGGCUCAAGAUUCCUCAAACAGCCAAUAAACAAUGCAAAGAAUAAAUGAGAGAGUAAUUGGAGACAAGCUUUCCCUUGGCUUCCCUUCUUUUCUCACAGAGGCUUUUCCAGAAGGUGGUCAUUUCCAUAGCCCAUGUGGAAUGAGAUGUCCACUAGGGCAGAGAAGCACAGAACCGUGGGCACUGCUUCCCUUCCUUUAACCCUAUCAUAUUGCUGCCCAGUGAGCAAUAUGGUCAUUGGUCAAGAAGGCUUAUGCCCAGGUAUCCCUGUGGCUAUGAGCAUUGCUCCUUAUCUAUGCCUCUGCUCUUAGACUUUUCCAUUCUGCCCUCUUAGGGGCCUUCCUGGCCAUGACCACACUACCUUAUUUUUCUCUAUAGUACUUAUCACCAUCUGACAUGUAUUUAUGUUUGUAUUUGUUUAUUGUCUGUCUCUACAAAUAAAAUGUAAAUUCCCUAAAAA